GUAAUUUUCCUGCGCCUCGGGGCGAGCAGCGGCGCGCAAGGAAAGAUCGGGUUCCGUUUUUCCCGCGGAUUCUGGUGCCUGUGGGGCCGGUGACCCAACACCAUGAAGGAAACGCCACUCUCAAACUGCGAACGCCGCUUCCUACUCCGUGCCAUCGAAGAGAAGAAGCGGCUGGAUGGCAGACAAACCUAUGAUUAUAGGAACAUCAGGAUCUCAUUUGGAACAGAUUACGGAUGCUGCAUUGUGGAACUUGGAAAAACAAGAGUUCUUGGACAGGUUUCCUGUGAACUUGUGUCUCCAAAACUCAAUCGGGCAACAGAAGGUAUUCUUUUUUUUAACCUUGAACUCUCUCAGAUGGCCGCUCCAGCUUUCGAACCUGGCAGGCAGUCAGAUCUCUUGGUGAAGUUGAAUCGACUCAUGGAAAGAUGUCUAAGAAAUUCGAAGUGUAUAGACACUGAGUCUCUCUGUGUUGUUGCUGGUGAAAAGGUUUGGCAAAUACGUGUAGACCUACAUUUAUUAAAUCAUGAUGGAAAUAUUAUUGAUGCUGCCAGCAUUGCUGCAAUCGUGGCCUUAUGUCAUUUCCGAAGACCUGAUGUCUCUGUCCAAGGAGAUGAAGUAACACUGUAUACACCUGAAGAGCGUGAUCCUGUACCAUUAAGUAUCCACCACAUGCCCAUUUGUGUCAGUUUUGCCUUUUUCCAGCAAGGAACAUAUUUAUUGGUGGAUCCCAAUGAACGAGAAGAACGUGUGAUGGAUGGCUUGCUGGUGAUUGCCAUGAACAAACAUCGAGAGAUUUGUACUAUCCAGUCCAGUGGUGGGAUAAUGCUACUAAAAGAUCAAGUUCUGAGAUGCAGUAAAAUCGCUGGUGUGAAAGUAGCAGAAAUUACAGAGCUAAUAUUGAAAGCUUUGGAGAAUGACCAAAAAGUAAGGAAAGAAGGUGGAAAGUUUGGUUUUGCAGAGUCUAUAGCAAAUCAAAGGAUCACAGCAUUUAAAAUGGAAAAGGCCCCUAUUGAUACCUCGGAUGUAGAAGAAAAAGCAGAAGAAAUCAUUGCUGAAGCAGAACCUCCUUCAGAAGUUGUUUCUACACCUGUGCUAUGGACUCCUGGAACUGCCCAAAUUGGAGAGGGAGUAGAAAACUCCUGGGGUGAUCUUGAAGACUCUGAGAAGGAAGAUGAUGAAGGCGGUGGUGAUCAAGCUAUCAUUCUUGAUGGUAUAAAAAUGGACACUGGAGUAGAAGUCUCUGAUAUUGGAAGCCAAGAGCUGGGGUUUCACCAUGUUGGCCAGACUGGACUCGAGUUCCUGACCUCAGAUGCUCCCAUAAUACUCUCAGAUAGUGAAGAAGAAGAAAUGAUCAUUUUGGAACCAGACAAGAAUCCAAAGAAAAUAAGAACACAGACCACCAGUGCAAAACAAGAAAAAGCACCAAGUAAAAAGCCAGUGAAAAGAAGAAAAAAGAAGAGAGCUGCCAAUUAAAGCUAACAGUUGUAUAUCUGUAUAUAUAACUAUUAAAAGGGAUAUUUAUUCCAUUCUGAGAACCCUGGGUAUUUUUUAUUCACAAAUCCAUUAUAAAAUCUAGCAGGAUUUUAAAAAUAGUUUUUUGUUUUUAAUGUGCUUUAAAAUAAUAAACCUUCUGGAGCA